AUGGGGGCUGUGGCCUUGUGGGUCCUGUGUGGCCUGGUGGGGGCUGUGGCCUUGUGGGUCCUGUGUGGCCUGUACAUCCUGGACUCACCUGUGAGCGGCUCCGGACAGGAGCCUUGCUGGGAAGACACUGAGUGUGAGAACUGGGCGUCGGUGCUGGGACCCUGUGGACACUGCGAGUGUGAGAACUGGGUGUCGGUGCUGGGACCCUGUGGACACUGCGAGUGUGAGAACUGGGUGUCGGUGCUGGGACCCUGUGGACACUGCGAGUUGACAGCCCUGGACGUGCUGUCGCCUCAUGAGGACGCCGAUGUGGCCCUGCUGCCGGAGUAUGCCAAGCACGAGGGGCCAGGUGGCACACAGCACCUGUGUGCCGCUGGGGAGGGUGACCGCGGGAGGAGCGCCCGUGCAUCGCUGCAGAGGGAGCUGGAGGCUGCCCCAGGCAGCGGCGUGGCUGGCGUGCGGAGUGUUUUGGGGGUGUCUGAGCUGGGUGGAGAGGAAGGCAUAUGUCACACUGAGGCAUCAGAGACACAUCCAUUCACGUCGGGGCUGUGUCCGCGCCGGGUCCACACUCAGUCAUCGCCCGUCCGCGCCGGGUCCACACUCAGUCAUCGCCCGUCCGCGCCGGGUCCACACUCGCGUCAUCGCCCGUCCGCGCCGGGUCCACACUCAGUCAUCGCCGUCCGCGCCGGGUCCACACUCGCGUCAUCACCUGUCUGCGCUGGGUCCACACUCGCGUCAUCACCUGUCUGCGCUGGGUCCACACUCGCGUCAUCGCCCACCCACGCCGGGUCCACACUCGCGACAUCGCCAUCCACGCCGGGUCCACACUCGCGUCAUCGCCAUCCACGCCGGGUCCACACUCGCGACAUCGCCAUCCACGCCGGGUCCACACUCGCGACAUCGCCAUCCACGCCGGGUCCACACUCGCGUCAUCGCCAUCCACGCCGGGUCCACACUCGCGUCAUCGCCAUCCACGCCGGGUCCACACUCGCGACAUCGCCCGCCCGCGCCGGGUCCACACUCAGUCAUCGCCCGUCCGUGCCGGGUCCACAUUCGCGUCAUCGCCAUCCACGCCGGGUCCACACUCACGUCAUCGCCAUCCACGCCGGGUCCACACUCGCGUCAUCGCCCACCCGCGCCGGGUCCACACUCGCGUCAUCGCCGUCCGUGCCGGGUCCACACUCAGUCAUCGCCGUCCGCGCCGGGUCCACACUCGGUCAUCGCCAUCCGCGCGGGGAUGUGUCUGAAAAGUGUGGUGAGAGCUGUGUUCCCUGCGCAUUUCUGAAGGCUCCUAGCCGCUGCAGUUGCCGGGAGCCAUGGAGCCACGUGACCUUGAGGUCCACCGGGGAGAGGAGGGUGCAUUUCGGAGGCUAGAAGUGGCACCUGGAGGGGCUGGCCCUGGGUGUGAUCAUUGAGAGGAGGGAGGUGGAAAAAGAUCUGGAAGAUGCCCUUGGGAAGCAGAAGAAGGUGGGUGACCAGAGUGGGGUGCCCAGAGGGUAGGGCAGGGCAGACCAGAGGAGGGGGUGGGCUUGGCACCCCCGGGAAGGAGGGAUGGGGCUCUGUGAAAGUGAGAGCUGUGUGGACGUGGAGCUUGUGAGUCUGACCAGGAAAGACAGAGGGUUCCAGACGGUGCGGGGGCCCCUUCAGUCUGGUUGUGUGGGGCAGGGUCCUCACCCCCAGGUGAGGGGGCCUUGUAGGGCAGAUUCCUGGAAGACCCUCAAGACGCAGGAGCGGAGGCUGCUGGCUGGAUGGGGAUGGAGCCGAGAGCUGAGCGGGCAGCCCAGGCCUGAAGGACAGCACAGGGGCCUCUGUGAGGCCAGGAGGGGCUGGAGUGCAACACCCCCUGUGACCCAGGUCUGGUGUGUGACGCGUCAGGCCCCACGGCACCGCAGGCUGGCUGGCUCCCCAGAAGGCCUGUGGUCUCCAUGGCCGCAGCGCAUUCCGGGGACAGGGCAGAGUGGAGUCAGCAGAGGGAGGAGGCGUGUGGGGCGUCCAGGGAUCAAGGGGUCUCUGGGCCUUGCUCCCUUCCCCAGCAGCUGUGAGGAUGGUGGGGGCUGCUGUCUGCCCAGGACUGCAAGCGUCAGGCACAGCAGCUGCUGUUAACAGUCAAGGAAUGUUCGGGCGUCACAAUGUAGCAGGGACCCCAGGCGUCGUGCUCAGAAAAUGGAAAAAGAGCCAGGGCCGGAAGGAGGGUGCAGAAGCGAGUCCGCGUGCGGAGCCAGGAGGCAGCGUCGCGUGGGAGUGCUGGCCUGAAGCCUCCAUGCCCCGGCAGAGGGACGGACACGCGGACGUCUAGCGGAGGCUCCCGUGUCCUCAGUAUGCAUCAGGUCUCCCGAACCUCACAGCCCCGCAGGGAGGAGGAGAAGGGGAGGAUUUGACUUUGGAAGUCUCUGUGACCAG